ACUAAAAGCAAGACAAGCAAGACAGAAGGGCUCAAGACUGGAGCAGCCAGGAAAUUCUGUCCAAGCCGAGUCCCUGGGUUUGCGAGACUUCACGCCACCUCACAGGGGUCGUCUGGGGUUGUGGUCUCUGGCCAGGAGGGUGCGGGAGCCUCUUUCUUCCAGCUCAGCUCGUGCUACACCAGAAAGGGAAGGGCAAGAGCACCCCCUCAACCCAGAGGACCCCCAGAUCAAGAGACCACCCAGGCUACAAUCAACUCUGAUGGCGCUUUUAAUCACCCCAGCAGGAGUGGCGACUGUAAACAGACAUUCAACAAUUCCCAGUGACACACAUACCUCCCGGGAAAAACCGCGUUUCCAUAAACCUUGCAGAAACGACUUGGAGAGCUUGCUGAGCGAGGGCCGCCUGGACACCAGUGUGCAGACGCCGUGUCCUCAGCACCCCCACACUCAGCUGUCCUGCGAGCCCCAGCCCCUGGAACACUCCAGCUGCCUCUCCACUUGUCUGGCGGGAUGUUUCCUCCCGGUGCCCUCAUCACCCCACACCCACCCUCUUCUCCCGGGCUCCCGAUGGCUCCCCCCACCACUUGCUCUGCUGAUGGGUACACUCUCCCCAGGUCUGGCUGUGAAGCCAUCCUGGGUGCCUCGGUUUCCCCUGCUGGCCAGGCAGUCACCAGCUACCUCAGUGGGAAUGCCACUCUCUGCCGCCACCCAGCCUGGGUCAGUGGGACGCCUGCACUUUCCCAAGUUGCGUUCCUCCAGCCCUUUCUCUGGACACUCGGAUGAGAACAAGGCUACUGGCCAAGGGCGUGAGAACAGGGAUCAGCCUCAGAGACCAUCCCAUCUCUGUGAGUGUCCUGAAGCUGCCAAGCAAAGUGCCACCAACGGGGUGGCUGAGACCAACAGAAGUGUAUUCCCUCUUGGUUCUGAGGCCAGAAGCCUGAGCUUAAGGCGUCAGGAGAGCCAGCCCCACUCUGGCAGCUCUAGAAGAGAAUCCGUUUCUUGCUCUCCCAGCUUCUGGUGUUGCUGGCAACCAUUAGCAUUCUUGACUUGUGGCUGCGCUGCUCCCAUCUCUGUCCCCGGGGUCACGCGGCCUUCUCCCCGGCCUUGCUGUGUGUCCCCUCCUCUUGUAAGACUCCAGUCACUGGGUUUAGGGCCCACACAAAUCUAGUAUGACCUCACCUUGACUUAAUCACAUCUGCAAAGGCCCUUCUUCCAAAUAAGGUCAUGUUCCCCAUUUCUGGGUAGAUGUAAAUUUAGGGGAGCUGCUAUGUAGCCCAGUGCCAUCCUCCUACAAACCCCAGGAUGGCCGAGGAAUCCAGUCUCAACUGAGAUGCAUCAGGCUGCUUAGGAUCAGAGCCCGGACCAUACUGAGCACUCACAUUCUCUCCUAAUAUUCUUUCAAGCAUUCCAGCAACAUCUAUUCCUGGAAACCCCAGGUCAAUCCCCCACCACCAGUGUUGCUGUUGCCUGGAGAAGAAAAUGCUCCAGACCCCUCCUUCCCAGCCUGCUGGGUUCCCUCCAACCCAGGCCCAGCCCCCUUCUCCAGGGAUUGAUAAGACGCCAUUUCCAGAUAUAUUGUUAAGUGGCAAAAGCAGACGGCAGUACGUAGUGACACAUCUUUUGUGUAAUAAAGUGUAAGGAUAUGUA